AGACGGAAGAGGAUGGCCGCGGCGGCUCUGAGGAGAUUUUGGUCCCGGCGCCGCGCAGAGGCGGGCGACGCGGUAGUGGCGAAGCCGGGAGUGUGGGCGCGGCUGGGGUCCUGGGCCCGCGCGCUGCUCCGGGACUACGCCGAGGCCUGCAGGGACGCUUCGGCGGAGGCUAGGGCCCGGCCGGGGCGCGCCGCUGUGUAUGUGGGUCUGCUGGGCGGCGCGGCGGCCUGCUUCACGCUGGCGCCCAGCGAGGGUGCCUUCGAGGAGGCGCUGCUGGAGGCGUCGGGGACCCUCCUGCUGCUGGCGCCGGCCACCCGCAACCGCGAGUCCGAAGCCUUCGUGCAGAGGCUGCUCUGGCUGCGGGGCCGUGGCCGCCUGCGCUACGUCAACCUGGGGCUCUGCUCGCUGGUGUACGAGGCGCCCUUCGACGCCCAGGCCAGCCUCUACCAGGCGCGUUGCCGCUACCUGCAGCCCCGCUGGACCGACUUCCCCGGCCGGGUCCUGGACGUGGGCUUCGUGGGUCGCUGGUGGGUGCUGGGGGCCUGGAUGCGCGACUGCGACAUCAACGACGACGAAUUCCUGCACCUGCCGGCGCAUUUGCGGGUGGUCGGGCCCCAGCAGCUGCAUUCCGAGACCAACGAGCGGCUCUUCGAUGAGAAGUACAAGCCUGUCGUGCUCACCGACGAUCAGGUGGACCAGGCGCUGUGGGAGGAGCAGGUCUUGCAGAAGGAGAAGAAGGACAGGCUCGCCCUGAGCCAGGCCCACUCGCUGGUGCAGGCGGAGGCCCCGAGAUGAAACCCUGAGGCCCCCGAGUCCUGGCAAACUGCUUGCCUGGGGUGGUGCAGUUCUGAGUGUGCCUCACCUGCAGAACAGCUGAGACAGAUGAUGUGCAAAGUGUUUUCUCACUGGAUUUGCACAAGUUUGGGGAGCCUUUCUGCCCCCCGUCUUUGUUCUUUAUUAGCUGAAGCUAAUUCAGAGCCACCUGGGUCCGGGAGUUGGGGACAGCAGAACGACUUGACACAUGUUCAUCACUGGCAGAGCUGGUCAUGAGCCUUUUAUAUAAGCCUUUUUCAUCGGGCCUCAGAGGCCCUCCUUAAGGAGGUACCACAUUGGUCAGCUGACUUGCAAACUCUUCUAAGGCCACUUAGAUUUUCUUUUUCAAGUUUGGGUUGUGGCCUGGCAUGGUGAUGUCUGUAAUCCCAGCAGUUUGCAAACUGAGGCAAGAGAAUCGCUUGAGGCCAGGAGUUUGAGGCCAGCUAGAGUGACAUAGCAAGACUCCGAUGCUACAAAAAAGAAUAAUAAUAGUAAUUAACUAAAUAAAAUUUGAGCUGAAAUGUUUUUAUUCUA